GAUUUCCUAAGUGUGGCUGAUGGUAGCCUCUAGUUUGAAGUGAGGGAAGAAUGAGUAGUCAGGAACUGGUCACUUUGAAUGUGGGAGGGAAGAUAUUCACGACAAGGUUUUCUACGAUAAAGCAGUUUCCUGCUUCUCGUUUGGCACGCAUGUUAGAUGGCAGAGACCAAGAAUUCAAGAUGGUUGGUGGCCAGAUUUUUGUAGACAGAGAUGGUGAUUUGUUUAGUUUCAUCUUAGAUUUUUUGAGAACUCACCAGCUUUUAUUACCCACUGAAUUUUCAGACUAUCUUAGGCUUCAGAGAGAGGCUCUUUUCUAUGAACUUCGUUCUCUAGUUGAUCUCUUAAACCCAUACCUGCUACAGCCAAGACCUGCUCUUGUGGAGGUACAUUUCCUAAGCCGGAACACUCAAGCUUUUUUCAGGGUGUUUGGCUCUUGCAGCAAAACAAUUGAGAUGCUAACAGGGAGGAUUACAGUGUUUACAGAACAACCUUCAGCGCCGACCUGGAAUGGUAACUUUUUCCCUCCUCAGAUGACCUUACUUCCACUGCCUCCACAAAGACCUUCUUACCAUGACCUGGUUUUCCAGUGUGGUUCUGACAGCACUACUGAUAACCAAACUGGAGUCAGGCUGGUAUGCAAUGGCGUGAUCUCGGCUCACCACAACCUCCGCCUCUGGGGUUCAAGUGAUUCUCCUGCCUCAGCCUCCCGAGUAGCUGGGAUUACAGGUAUGUUUCUAUAAAACCUGAUAACCGAAAAUUGGCCAACGGAACAAAUGUCCUCGGCUUACUGAUUGACACUUUAUUAAAGGAAGGCUUUCAUUUGGUCAGCACUAGAACAGUAUCUUCUGAAGACAAAACUGAAUGCUAUAGCUUUGAAAGGAUAAAAAGCCCUGAAGUGCUCAUCACGAAUGAAACACCAAAACCAGAGACUAUCAUCAUACCAGAGCAAUCUCAGAUAAAGAAAUGAAGUUGUCUAUCCUCUUUUAAAGAGAAAUUGCCAUUUUUCUUGUUUCAUUACGUAUUUAGGGCAUACAUGUUAGCCAAAUCUACACUCAGCCUAACUCUUGGCUUCAUCUGCUGCCAUGCCGUCUCUGGGCAACCAGGCCCCAACUGUGCUUAAGCCAUAAUGCCUGCUGCUCUCUAGACAACUCCAUGUACUUGGUGCUUUGGUAUAUGUUCUACCUUCAAUACAUCUUUCCCUUUCUCUUCUUCAUGAAUGCUUAUGAGCCGAGAUUGCGCCACUGCACACUAGCUUGGGUGACAGAGGAAGACUGUCUCAAAAAAAAAAAAAUUGAUCAAACUGAUGGAUACCCUAAGUACCCUGACUUGAUCAUUACACCUUCUAUGCAUGCAACAAAAUGCCACGUGUACCCCAUAAAUAUGUAGAAAUAUUAUAUGUAAAUAAAUAGUUGGGCCUUCCGUAUUUUCCCACUUA